ACACGCUCAGCCGAGCCCAGUCUGGGAGGGACGCGCCCGGCAGCUGUCCACCGAUCCCGGCCACCGCCCCCGGCCACCCCCACCCCGCGAGCCCAUGGAGGCUCCGGGACCCCGCGCCUUGCGGACUGCGCUCUGUGGCGGCUGUUGCUGCCUCCUCCUAUGUGCCCAGCUGGCUGUGGCUGGUAAAGGAGCUCGAGGCUUUGGGAGGGGAGCCCUGAUCCGCCUGAAUAUCUGGCCGGCGGUCCAAGGGGCCUGCAAACAGCUGGAGGUCUGUGAGCACUGCGUGGAGGGAGACGGAGCGCGCAAUCUCUCCAGCUGCGUGUGGGAGCAGUGCCGGCCAGAGGAGCCAGGACACUGUGUGGCCCAAUCUGAGGUGGUCAAGGAAGGUUGCUCCAUCUACAACCGCUCAGAGGCAUGUCCAGCUGCUCACCACCACCCCACCUAUGAACCGAAGACAGUCACAACAGGGAGCCCCCCAGUCCCUGAGGCCCACAGCCCUGGAUUUGACGGGGCCAGCUUUAUCGGAGGUGUCGUGCUGGUGUUGAGCCUACAGGCGGUGGCUUUCUUUGUGCUGCACUUCCUCAAGGCCAAGGACAGCACCUACCAGACGCUGUGAGUACCUGGCCAGCAGCAAGUACCUGAGUCCCAGCUUACCUCCUGGUUCCUGCCCCACCGUUCCCCUUCAGUACCCAGGGUGCUGUCUUCUCCAUGGGCAAGCCCUCAGGACGGUGACAGCGUGCUCCAUGUGAGCCACACCCCUUUUGUCUCCUCCAGUUGGGGUGUUUCCUUUGUCAGAUGUUGGCUGGGACCAGGACUCAGCCUGGGCCAGUCUAGGAGCCCAGCUGAGCCCUCCUGUGUCUUUUCCCUUCAUGCUGCCAGCAGGGAAGAGAACCAGUAGGUGCCAGCCCAGGCAAGCCUGUGGCCCGCGUUUCUGUGGCUGUGGGCAGGAGCUGGGCCUUGUGUCUAGUUGGGUUUUGCUCUGAGAAGGGGAGCUGUGCCUGAGGCCCUCUGUGUGCCGUGUGUGCUGUGGGGCGGGUCGCCACAGCCUGUGUUAAAGUGUUUGCUCUUCCUCUGCUGCCUCCUCUCGAGGCAGGGGGUCCUUGGCUGGCUGAGGCAGUGUCACCUUCCUGAGUGUCCUCUUUGGCCUCUGCAGAAUCUGACCCCUUUGGGCCUGGACUCCAUCCUGAGGGGAAAGGAGGAUGCAGAGGGUGGCCUCUGGGCACCCUUGUGGGUAAGCGGGGGGCGGGGGCGGGAAAAACUCUGGCCGCCAGUUUUUGGCUCCUGCGGGCACCAAGCAGGCUCAGUGUCUGAUGCCUGACAUCUCCUCCUGUCCUGGGCCUGGAACCUGCAGCUGAGAAAAUCCCUCAACCACCUCGUCUCCUCCAUCGCCCCUGCUGGGCCCCCCAGCCUGACAGUGGGUUGUAUGCCUGCCUCUUUCCACCAACUGGCCUGGGCACUGCCCCCAAAUAAAGGAACUCUGCACUGCA